AGUGAGCAAAUCGCGGACCACCGGGGCUGCCAGCUCGCCUGACUCCCGGCCUCUUGCGCUCCUAGGGGCGGAGAAGGGUGCGGGCUCUUCGCCCUUUGUGUCCUCCUUCUUUCACUAACUUCUGGACUUUCCAGCUCUUCCGAAGUUCGUUCUUGCGCAAAGCCCAAAGGCUGGAAAACCGUCCACGAUGACCAGCAUGACUCAGUCUCUGCGGGAGGUGAUAAAGGCCAUGACCAAGGCUCGCAAUUUUGAGAGAGUUUUGGGAAAGUAACACGUGGAGGAACAUACGUUGGGAAUAUCAACUGACACGCACUGUGCUAGGAUCUAGAAAUACCAUGUGGACUCCAACACACAUAGAAAUAAGGAAGUGGAAUUCCAAAGGAAGGCAAAGUGUAAAGUCAUCUUUAUGGAAAUGAGUGAUGAAGGUGAAUACCUGAAUGAGAUGUCAAGAGGAGGAACACACUGGAGAGAAGCAGUAAAGAUUUAGGACUGAACCUUAAAGACAUACAGGCUUGAGAGAAAGAAAGCAUGUAAAGAAGACAGAAAUGGUUAGAAAGAUUACUCUUGUCUCUGCUGCUCCUGGGAAAGUGAUUUGUGAAAUGAAAGUAGAAGAAGAGCAUACCAAUGCAAUAGGCACUCUCCACGGCGGUUUGACAGCCACGUUAGUAGAUAACAUAUCAACAAUGGCUCUGCUAUGCACGGAAAGGGGAGCACCCGGAGUCAGUGUCGAUAUGAACAUAACGUACAUGUCACCUGCAAAAUUAGGAGAAGAUAUAGUGAUUACAGCACAUGUUCUGAAGCAAGGAAAAACACUUGCAUUUACCUCUGUGGAUCUGACCAACAAGGCCACAGGAAAAUUAAUAGCACAAGGAAGACACACAAAACACCUGGGAAACUGAGAGAACAGCAGAAUGACCUAAAGAAACCCAACAAUGAAUAUCAAGUAUAGAUUUGACUCAAACAAUUGUAAUUUUUGAAAUAAACUAGCAAAACCAGAAGCAGCUAGAAAUAUUCUUGGAGGAAAAGGACCUGGAUAUCAAGUAGGGUAAAGGUGGGGGUGUCUUUUUUCACUUUAAGCAUCUUGUUUUCUAAUCAUGUGUGAUAAUUGGGUGAAAAAUUCUUAGCUCAAAGUGUUUUAAAAACAGGUAAAGCAAAGAAACUAGCAGGACCACUCUCAGUUAAGAUUAAAACUAAAGUCCAGUGUUAAGCUAAAGGAGAAAUAGAAAUUAAUGGUUCUAAUUCUGUUUGGGCUGCUAGGAACAACAGAAAUUUUUCAUGGUUCUAGAAGCUGGAAAGUCCUGGGUCAAGGCCCAGCAGAUCCUGUUAGGUGAGGGCCCGCUUCCUGGCUCAUAGAUGGUGCCUUCUCACUGUGUGGUGGAAGGGGCAAGUGAGCCCUCUGGGUUCUCGUUUUUGAAAUGGAGUCUCGCUCUGUUGCCCAGGCUGGAGUACAGCAGCACGAUCUCGGCUCACUGCAAUCUCUGCCCCCUGGGUUCAAGUGAUUCUCCUGCCUCAGCCUCCCAAGUAGCUGGGACUAUAGGCAUGUGCCAUCACACCUAGCUAAUUUUUGUAGUUUUUUGUAGAAACAGGGUUCACCAUGUUGGCCAGGCUGGUCUCGAACUCGUGACCUCAGGUGAUCCGCCUGCCUUGGCCCCCCAAAGUGCUGGGAUUACAGGUGUGAGCCAAUGUGCCCAGCCUGGGUUCUCUUUUGUAAGGGCACUUACUCCAAUCUUGAGGGUUCUGCCCUCGUGAUCUAAUAACUUCCCAAAGACCCCCACCUGCUAAUAUCACCUUGGGGGUUGGGAUUUUAACAUACAAAUUUAGGGGAAACACAUGGAGACCACAGCAAUGGCCAAUCCUUAGCGAAUCUUAGGUCCUUCCCAGAUCUAAAAUGCCAAGCUACACUUGCAUUUCCUUUUUUUAAGAUUAUGAAACUUCAAAAUAUAUGAACUACAGCCCAUAUUGAAAAAUAAAAUAGAUUGAGCCAUAUGCCUAAAAAAGACCUCAAGAAAAGUUUGAGGCUAAGCAUGUUAGUGUUACAGGAAAUGGUCCAAUAGAGGGGGAAGAAAAAAAGCAUGCUACUAGCCCCUUUUCUUGUACCGAGAAUAAAACCAUGCAGAUCUCAAACCUCCAAGUCUAUAGUAUUGAAAAGACCAAGUUCACUUCUCAGAAGUCUCCAAGUUCAGUUGACUGUGGCACUCUGAGACAGCUUCUGUCACUCAGGCUGGAGUGAUACAAUCACAGCUUCCCAUAGCCUCAAAAUCCCAGGCUCAAGACAUUCUUCCACCUCAGUCUCCUGAGUAGCUGGAACUACAGGCGUGUGCCACCACGCCUAAUUUUAUUUUUGUAGAAACAAGGUCUCACUGUUGCCCAGCCUCGUCUCAAACUCCUAGGCUCAAGCAAUCCUCCUGCCUUGGCCCCCCAAGUACUGGACUUACAGGUGUGAACCACUGCACCCAGCUGACUCUUACUUGAUUUCUGUCAGGGAAUCUUAAUGAACAUUUCAUGACUAAAGACUAAAAAGGAUGCAGCUUUAAGUAAAUUUAAGUCAAGUUAACAGUUAAAGACAAAUCCUUUCCCUACAUUAGAUCGCCUGCUGAUCUGUCCACUGUGAAAGGGCAGAAGACUCCACAGUAGCAAUAGCAGCAGUGAGCAUACAGGAGUCCCAGAUGUUUACUUCUAGUAUUUCCCACUAAAAGGAAGCUGGGCUCCUUGGAGAAACAGCUGACUCCAGGGCUUGAGGCUGGGACAGAAAGGUUACAGUAUCUUAUGCAUGAAAGGAGAUGCUCAAAAUAAUAAAGGCAUGCAAAUUAUGAUUUGGAGGGAAAAAAUAUGAGGCCAUAGUGUUUAGGUAGAUAAUAAAUGGCAGAGAUAGAACACUCUCUUACAACAAAUGCUGUAAAUGGACAAAGCAUUAGAUUUGGAAAAUCACUAUUUUGUAACCAUCAUAGUUAAAGACUGGUUUGGGUUUUAGUCUGGAAAGAAUCGCCAAGGGAGCUCCUGAUAAAGGAACAGGGUAUUUGCACAUUGCUUCCCAGAGAUUGCUAGUAGUAAGUACCACACAUAGGGCAAAACCAGGACACCUUGACCAGGCGCUCAAAAGUAACAUCAAUGAAGAGCAGAUGGAGAGUAUACUUGAGAAGGGCGUUAAGCAUGAAUAAACAAUUCAAAUGCAAAAUGAGUAACAAUUUACAAGAAAAAUUGCCCUGUACUCCAAAAAACAUAGAGGUCAUGGAACACAUAAAGGCUAAGGAACUGUUCCACAUUAAAGACAACUGAGAACAACUAAAUUCAAUGAUCCUGUACUCUAGAGGGGGGGAUCUAAAACAAGCUACCAAGGAUACUGGGACAACAAAACGAAUAUGGAUGAUAAAGAGUAUCAACAUUCCCUGAGUUUGGUAAUUUUACUCUAGUUAUAUGAAAUAUUCUUGUACUUGGAACAUAUGCCGAAGUACUAAGGAAGGGGUAAGGAAGCACAAAGUGUGCAACAAACUCAAAUAGCUCACAGGUAUAAGUGUACAGAGAAAAUGAAAAAAAUGUGGCAAAAUAAUAAAAAUGAGGGUAAAGAUUACACAACAGCUUUCAUAUUACUCUGGUAACUUUUCUAAAUUAUUCCAAAAUAAAAACGUAAACAAUGGCUGCCAAAAUGCCUAACUUGGUGAACAUAAGUGUAAUUCAAUAUGGUAAAUUAAUUCAACAUGGUAAAUUAAGAGCAUAGGCCUUAAGAGCCAGCCAGCCUGGUUUUAAAUCCUCCACUACUUAUGAUCUGAGCUUGAGCAAGUUACUUAACCUCUGCAUCUAUUUCCACCAAAGGUUGAGAGGUUAAGACAAGAGCUUAGAAGAGUACCUGGUUAUAAUAAACAUUCAAAAUGUUAUUUCAAAUAGAUUCUAAUUUUUAAAUAAGAGGACACAUGAAAGCAUUUUGAAAUUUAAGAAUGGCCCUUUCCCAUGAAGCAAGGCAUAAGGCCAGGUUGCUAACUGUUGAAAGCUGACAGUAUGUUCUUGAUUCCUGUUCUUGUUGAAGUUACACACUCAAUUGCCAGGUAUUUUUCUUCUGAAUUUACUAUUUAGCCACAGACUAUGAAAUAAUUCUCUAAGGUGACCAGUAACAUCAGUGAAAUGGAAAGAAAAAGUUAACACUUCAAACUUUGUGUAUUCACCUGAAUAGUCAGGGAACUUUCACCUAUUUUAUUUAGGUUUUCUUUUUCUUUUUUUCUUUUUUUUUCAAAUUCCAACCAGAAGCUAAAUACAAUUGGAAACUGGUAAGCACUAGUUUUACUCCAAAGGAGUAGGAUCAUUCAGAUUUACUCCAAUAAAAGUAUGCAACCCUUAA